GUGUCCCUCCGCGGCGGCUGCGAGGCGGUGCGGCGGCUGAGGCGGCCGAGGCGGCCAGUUGGGUACCGGGAGGGGCGAAGGCGGGCGGCAGAGGCGAUCAGGUGGGUGUCCGGGAGGGGCGAAGGCGGGCGGCAGAGGCGGCCAGGUGGGUGCCCGGGAGGGGUGAACUUAGGCGGCGAGGAGACCGAGUUCUCAGGAAGGGCGAACCCUGGCGGCGGGGAAGCUGGAUCCCUCAGACGGGCGAACUUAGGCUACGGGGAGGCCGAGCCUUCAGGAAGGGCGAGGCCGGGCGCGGUGGCUCACGCCUGUAAUCCCAGCACUUUGGGAGGCCGACGCGGGUGGAUCACCUGAGGUCGGGAGUUCGAGACCAGUCUGGCCAACAUGGUGAAACCCCGUCUGUACCAAAAAUACAAAAUUAGCCGGACGAGGUGGCGCGCACCUGUAAUCCCAGCUGCUGAGGAGGCUGAGGCAGGAGAAUCACUUGAACCCAGGAGGCAGAGGUUGCAGUGAGCCGAGAUCACAUCACUGCACUCCAGCCUGGGCAACCAGAGCGGGGGAAAAAAAAAAAAGAACAAAAGAAAAAAGAAAAAAGGAAGGGCGAACUCAGGCGGCAGGGAAGCCGGAUCCUUCAGGAGGGGUGAACUUAGGCGGCGAGGAGGCCGAUCCCCCAGGAGGGGCGAACGCGGGCGGCGGGGAGACCGAUUACCCCGGAGGGGGAUACAGGGUGCGGGGUCGAGCUGCGGGGGUGAACUCCUGGCCCUGCCCGCUGCCCUCCCGCAGGACCCCGCACCUCCCGGUGUGGAUUAAAAUUCUGCAGGGCUUCAGGAUCCCCAAGCCAACGCGGCGGUCGGGCCCUUUCGAAUAGGCCCUUCUUGCUCGGGGUCCCCAAAGUCGCUGGCAGGGCCCCCCCACCCCGGAAGGAGGCGCCCGCCAGGGACAAGCUGCCCCUCCUCCCUGCAGCGAAGAGGGGCUAGAAAGUGUAAGCGAGGGUGCAUUUUAUUAGGAGUCACUGAGAGGGGAGGGGAAAUUGGAAAAUGCAGUCACAGAGCAGAAAAUCAGUGCUCCAAGCCGCAGCUCAUCCUGGGGAAGUUUCCAAGGGUCACUUGUGUCUCGUCCGUGGGAAGACCGGGGGAGCCCAGAAGGCCUUGGUGUGGAAUUCUGAGAGCUGAUUCCUGCCUUGUCUUCUCCACUGUUCCUGGAGGAAUCCGAGAAGAGCAGAGCGGAGGGAGCCCCAGACACGGUCCGCGGGAGAGCUGUGGGGCUUGGUGAGUGUUUCGUGGCCUCUCGGGUUGGUCAGCACCCCCAGCCAGCUGGCCCAGGACCCCUCUACAGAAGUCCAGGAGAGCAGGCGUCACCAAGAUGUCCAACCCCUUCCUGAAGCAAGUCUUCAACAAGGACAAGACAUUCCGCCCCAAGCGCAAGUUUGAGCCAGGCACCCAGCGCUUCGAGCUGCACAAGAAGGCGCAGGCGUCGCUGAACGCCGGGCUGGACCUGCGGCUGGCCGUGCAGUUGCCCCCGGGCGAGGACCUGAACGACUGGGUGGCUGUUCACGUGGUGGACUUCUUUAACCGCGUCAACCUCAUCUACGGCACCAUCAGCGACGGCUGCACGGAGCAGUCCUGCCCCGUCAUGUCGGGGGGCCCCAAGUAUGAGUACCGCUGGCAGGAUGAGCAUAAGUUCCGGAAGCCCACGGCACUCUCCGCGCCCAGGUACAUGGACCUGCUGAUGGACUGGAUCGAGGCGCAGAUCAACAACGAGGACCUCUUCCCCACCAACGUUGGCACUCCGUUUCCCAAGAACUUCCUGCAGACGGUGCGGAAGAUCCUGUCGCGGCUGUUCCGCGUGUUCGUGCACGUCUACAUCCACCACUUUGACCGCAUCGCGCAGAUGGGCUCCGAGGCCCACGUGAACACCUGCUACAAGCACUUCUACUAUUUCGUCAAGGAGUUCGGCCUCAUCGACACCAAGGAGCUGGAGCCACUGAAAGAAAUGACCGCCCGGAUGUGCCACUGAGAGCCCCGCGGGUCUCCCGGUGCCCGAACCGCCGCUGGGGCCUCGGAGACUUGGAGGAGGACGCUCUGGAACCAUCAUCCCGCUUCUCUCCGGCCUGAGCAUCUCAGGGAGACCAGGGGCCGAGCCGCUGAGCAGGUGUUGGUCCUCAGGAGCUCCAACCCCGGACGGCAGAUGCCUUCCUCAGUCUCGAGCCUCAGUCUCCCGUCUGGGACUAAAACGUGAACUCUGUAAUUCUAUGUGUUACUAGCAACCGGAAAAGCCCACUGUGUUUUUAAACCACUUCCACUUUCCAGGAGGCUGGAUGGCUUCCAGGGUCACUCCUUGCCCUGGGUGGCUCCCAGGCUCCUGGAACUUCUGCCUCCACCUCGCUGGGGAGCCCCCAGGGCUGCUGUGGCCACAGCCCUGCCUGGGCCUGUCUCUCAAGGGCACCCAGCUUGCUCGGCCUCCUACAUGUCUCCCGUUGGGGAGGCAAGAGGCUGAGGGGCUUCCGAGCCCCUGAGAGCGGACAUCUCCUCCCGCAGGCCUUUACUCCGCACUCCCCACUGGCAGCCGCUGGUGUCUCUUCACACAGAGGCACAACCUGGACCCAGGCAGCCUCUUUCCUCCCUCCCCAAUCUCUUCCAUUUUUCUACAGAUUUUUUUUUUUUUGGUCAUACUAGAGACAGGGGUCUCGCUGAACUCCUGGCCUCCAGUGAUCCUCCAUCCUCGGCCUCCCAAAGUGCUGGAAUCACAGGGGUGAGCCACCGCACCCAGCCCUCUCUCUUCCUCAAUGCACUCUGCUUCUUCCGUUCUUCCGAAACAUUCAGCUGACUGUAUCCAGGGCUUCCUGGACUCCUGGGACCCCACGUCCUGCACCCCGGCUUCUGACUCAUUUCCUAAGGGCCCCUUUGUGUAUCAUAAAGGGUUUGAUUUUUAUAGUCACAUUUACAACCAUCUUGAGAUUUUUAUUUUUUUUGAACGGAGUCUCCCACUGUCGCCCAGACUGGAGUCCAGUGGCACAAUCUCGGCUCACUGCAUCCUCCACCUCCUGGGUUCAAGUGAUUCUCCUGCUUCAGCCUCCCAAGUAGCUGGGAUUACAGGUGUGCGCCACCACGCCCAGGAAAUUAUUGUAGUUUUAGUAGAGACAAGAUUUCACCAUGUUGGCCAGGCUGGUCUCAAACUCCUGACUUCAGGUGAUCCGCCUACCUUGGCCUCCAAAAGUGCUGGGAUUACAGGCAUGAGCUACUGCACCCGGCCUAACCAGGCUGGAGUGCAGUGGUGGGAUCUCGGCUCACUGCAAGCUCCGCCUCCCAGAUUCACGCCAUUCUCCUGCCUCAGCCUCCCCAGCAGCUGGGACUACAGGCACCCACCGUCACACCCGGCUAAUUUUUUUGUAUUUUAGUAGAGACAGGGUUUCACCGUGUUAGCCAGGAUGGUCUUGAUCUCCUGACCUUGUGAUCCACCAGCCUCAGCCUCCCAAAGUGCUGGGAUUACAGGCGUGAGCCACUGUGCCCGGCCAAGAAUUUUUUUAUCGAUAACAUAGUGAGCUCUCUGCCUCUUCGGAACGAUGUCCACUUUGCUUAUGAUCAACCCAAGCAGGACUCUUCUCUCCCUGGACGCCUCUCCCCUGGUCUGGAAUCUUCCAGUUCUGCCAGAAUUGGCCUUUCCCAGAUGCUGCAAACUUCCAGUUGAACCCCUUUUUCUGUGUGGCCCCUGGGGCUGCGAGACCAAAAUCCAUGAGUUCUGUGUACCCUAGACCUUUGGAAGGUGAGAGCAGGGCCCUGAGAAAAGGCAGCCACCUCCUCUCCCUGGCUGAACCCCUGCCACCCUACUCCUCACCAGAAUUGUCAGUGGCCUUUCACCACAGUGGUCCUUCCUGCCUGAGCCCUGCACUGUCCCAGACCACACAGAAGUCUGGUCACCUCUGGGCGCCUGGGAUGGUCACCGAAGAGAAGCACGCUGUCCCCGUCUCUCCUGGCUUCUGCCAGAAAAUCGAACAAGUGCAAUUAACACACUGUUACUGCCGAAGCCUGAAACUCCCAGGACUUGUCCUUGAUCCUUCCAGAAACCACCAGGUCCGGCACUUGGAGCCCCCCGGAGAGGGACCUCCCAGCCGAGCCCUCAAAGAACUCCAUGAAAUCAGGAACUGCUUGAUGAAAUGUAUCUCCUUGUACCUGGAAGAUGAAGCCCAAACACCCACACCUCUGUCUCCCCCAGGGCUCGGGAUGUCUCCAGCAGCCCGGCCACGCAGCUUCCCAGGUGGGCUCGGGGAGGUGGGAGCAGGGACCAUCUCUGUCCCCUCCACCCUCACUCCAUCCACCUCGGAGACCACCCUCCCCCAGCCAGAUACGGAAUAAAACUACAGACGCAGACGUCGGAA